CCUUUGGCGCGUGAGUGACAGCGGCCCAGACAGAGGGGGCGAUGUCCGCGUCGUGGCUGGGGCCGGUCGCGGGGCAGACUAAUCCCCUGCUCCUGGCCAGGGGAGGCUCCCGAGCGGAUCCUCGGGAAAGGGGCUCCGAAGGUCAAGAAACUGCCCUGCUGGGCGUCCGGGGAGUGGGAAAAUAAAGCACUUUUUGUAUCCCGCCCCUCCCCCGUCACGUGACCACGCGAGGCGGAAAGAAGAAAUCCGAGGACCGGCGACGCCUAGAACAGGAGCCCAUGAUGCUGCCCAAACCUGGGACCUAUUACCUCCCCUGGGAGGUUAGUGCAGGCCAAGUUCCUGAUGGGAGCACGCUGAGAACAUUUGGCAGGUUGUGCCUCUAUGACAUGAUUCAGUCCAGAGUAACACUGAUGGCUCAGCACGGAUCCGAUCAGCACCAGGUUCUUGUCUGUACCAAGUUGGUGGAGCCCUUCCACGCCCAGGUGGGCUCCCUGUACAUCGUCCUCGGGGAGCUCCAGCAUCAGCAGGACAGAGGCUCCGUGGUGAAGGCGCGCGUGCUGACCUGUGUGGAGGGGAUGAACCUGCCCUUGUUGGAACAAGCCAUCCGGGAGCAGAGACUGUACAAGCAGGAGCGGGGCGGCAGCCAGUAGGAAACAGCAGCCUAGCAACACCCUCACCUGCUUCAGAGCCCGAACCCUCUGGAGCUGCAGGAGCCCGGGAGAGCACAGACGCCUCCCCAGCGACGGCCUUGUCUGGAGCUCGAAAGCCGAGGGGCGGGUGAUGAAUCCAGCCCCUUCCCCUACUUUGGGAUUGGCUCAGCAAUGAGAACCCAGAAAGCAUGCCAUAAAUCCGACAGCCCCACCCCAGGAGACUGCAGGUGGCCGAGCUUGGGCGCCGGGGCCGUGCUUGGUGUGGGGCCAUGGAGGGUUCCAGAAGGUCCUGGUGAAUAAAGGCCCAGGGGGCGUGCUCUUGAA